UGGCCUCAAGCAGUCCUCCCGCCUCAGCCUCCCAAAGUGCUGGGAUUACAGACAUGAGCCACCACCCAACCUCAUGUUCUAACUGAUAAAACUUACAAGUUUAUAAAACUUAUAAAAUUCUCAGAAAGUGAAAACUGAUUUGAGAAAUGACCUGGAUAUGAAAAACUAAGUACAGAUCCUUUAGCGACUUACAAGUUGGUUGACUUUGGUGACAUCACUUUGUCUCUCUUGACCACUAUAAAAGAAGGGUUUGGAGAGAUUCCCAGCUAUGGGCCAAGGACUAGUUACAUCAUAAUCACCUGGGGCCAUUGUUAAAAAGUCACAUUCCCACACCUUUUCACAGUUCUGAAUCAAUCUCCUGAAUGGGAAUGUUUUCCUAGCAAACAAUCCAGGUUUUUGUGAGGUGGAGAAAAGCAGAGUGACCUGGGAGAAGUGGUUAUCAACAACACAGCUGGUGACUUCUUCCCUGGGGGCAAGCUUCGCUGCUGAGUUGCUUGGAGGAGCUUGGAGAAACCAGAAGUGAGAUCCAGGAGAAGUAAGGCCCUGGAGUGCCAGGAGCCCUUCUCCCAAAGAUGGAGAAAUAAAUGAAGAAAUACAGGAAAAUAAGCAUUGGGUGUUUUGCAAUGGCUACACAAACUAGUCAUGUCUUCCAUGGUCAAGAAAAUAUGUUUCUGGAAAACCAUUGCAUUAGGAGAAACACUGGCAGAGAUUCAAAGAAGCCACUAAAGCAGAAGAAUAUGAAUGGACUUGGGCAAAAUUCGGACAAUGGAUUAUUGGUUACACAUGUUAACCAGACACAGGACUUACUGAGGCUGCAGGGGAGUGAGACCCAGUCUUCAGAUUGGGAGGACUCUGAAGACUGGCUUUCGGCUCACAGUUUAAAAUGUCAGAAACUCACCUUGGCUGACCUGAUAAGCCAGGGCACAGAAGUGCUGGAGGAGGGCACCAAUGUCGUGCAGAAAAUAUGUUUCUCCACCCAGAUCAUCCGCCAUUUUGAGUCAAAGCUUUCUGACACUAUUGAAGUCUAUCAAGAGAGAAUUCAGUGGCUCACAGAAAACAGCAAGAAGCAAAAUUGGAGGCAAAAUCACUUGCUGGGAGAGUACAGAAAGGGAGUGCUGGAGGCAUUUGGCCUCAUCAAAGGGGCCAGAGUCAGCAUCCUCAUAGAUGUGUCAGCCAUCAGCAGUGGCCCUCAGAAAGAAGAGUUCCAAAAGGACCUCAUGAGCCUCAUCGAUGAGCAGCUGAGCCACAAGGAGAAGCUGUUUGUCCUGUCCUUUGGCACCAAUGCCGGGUCCCUCUGGCCAGACCCCAUGGAAGUCAGCGCCUCCACCCUCCAGGAACUUAAGCUCUGGGUAAAGACGCUGCAGCCUGAUGGAGGCAGCAACCUGCUACAAGCUCUGAAGAAGAUCUUCACUCUCAAGGGACUGGAUUCCCUGGUGGCCAUCAUGAGAAGCUGCCCAGAUCAGCCUUCUGAAAUCCUGUCUGACUACAUCCAGCAGUCCACCAUGGGAAGAGACCUCAUCAUCCACUUCAUCACCUACAGAUGCGAUGAUCAGAUGCCCCCUGCUGUCCUGAAGAACCUUGCAGAAGCUGUUAGGGGCUACUACCACUGCUACAGCCCAAAGAUGGAGCACUACACCAGCCGGGACAUGGAUGAGCUCCUGGCAGAAAUUCAGAAGGCCCAGAGCCUCCUCAGCCACGUGCAAGCCCUGCAGCACAGCAGCCCCUGUGAGGCGCUCACCUGCACCAUGGAGGAGAUUUCCACAGAGAUUACAAAUGGGCCACUCAUAAGCCUCUUGCCUAAACCCCCAAAGCAUGACGCUCCUCUCACCAUUGAGUUUCCAAACUUGGACAAGACUUCUGCAGAGUGGCUUAAGGUCAAUGGUCUGAAAGCCAAGAAAUUAAGUCUAUAUCAGGUCCUGGCACCCAAUGCAUUCUCUCCUGUGGAGGAAUUUGUACCUAUUCUCCAGAAAACAGUAUCAUCGACCAUCCAUGAGAAGGCAAUGAUACAAUUUGAAUGGCACGACGGGACAGUGAAGAACAUUCAUGUGGACCCACCCUUCCUCUAUAAGUACCAGUGGAAUGAUUAUACUGCCUGGAUUCCCAGGGACUUGACACACCAUUCCCUGAAGCCCACCCAGCAACAGCUCAGCAGAGCUAUGCGGAUGUAUGAGAGGCGGAUUGAGUGGCUCUCCCUGGCCAGCAGAAGAAUCUGGGGCACAGUCUGUGAAAAAAGGGUGGUUGUACUGCUCGAUAUCUCUGCGACCAAUUCCAUGUACAUUAUUCAUAUCCAGCACUCCCUGCGGCUGCUGCUGGAGGAGCAGUUAUCCAACAAGGACUGUUUCAACCUCAUCGCGUUUGGAAGCACAAUUGAAAGCUGGAGGCCUGAGAUGGUUCCCGUGAGUCACAACAAUUUACAAAGUGCCUGGCGGUGGGCCCUGAACCUGCGGUGUCGGGGCAGCAGGAACGUUCUCAGCGCCCUGCGGAAGGCUGUGGAAGUAGACUUCAAGGACAAAGACAAACACCAAUCGCAGGGAAUCUACCUCUUCACUGGGGGCAUCCCCGACCAGGACAUGCCUACACUCAGUGCCUACAUGGCUGAGGCCUGUGGCGGCUGCGACCUCCAGCUGAACGUGUGUCUCUUCUACGUGGGCGAGCCAAAGAUGGACACCACACCCCCUGCCCGCUAUGCCAGUCACACUGACACAGCCGCCGCCUACAAGGAGGUCACCCGGGCUGCAGGUGGCCGCUUCCACUGGUUUGGAGACACAGGCAUUUAUGAGAGCGAUGACAUCAACUCCAUCAUGUCUGAGAUGGAAAAGGCUCUCAACUACUCCCAAAAGUGUGCCUUCCUCAUGGCCUCCCUGAAGAACCAUUCAGGAAAAGUACUGGGAAGUUCAGCCCUCCCGAAAGAAAAACCAAAGACACUUCAGCUAAGAAGUCAGCCCAAGAAGCUCUGCCCUCCCAGGCCCACCGUCCCCCUGGGGGCCAGAAUGAGCAUUAAAGAUGACCCUGACAGAGAGAAGAGCCCCCCGCUGAAAUCUCUGAAAUGGCGUCCACUCAGUAGCAGAGUUGGCAUCUCACCAGCUGCGGCCCAGCCAACGAAAGAAGGGAUGAUGGAACUGAGGAGGAAGACCAAGUCAAGGGAAGCAGAGACAUCUCUUUUACUGUUCUACACAGAGAAAGGGAAUGACGUGGGCUCAGUGUACAAGAAGUACCCUCAAGGAAGGGGCUUGAGAAGGACUAGCUCUUCUAUUGACUUACCCAGAAAGGAUACAGUUUGCUCAAGCCAAGAGUGGGUGGCAAAAUAUGGGCUCAAAAAAUUGAAGCUGGAGAUUUCCAGAUGCAUGGGUCCCAACUGCACUCAUCAAAAGUCAGGACAGAGGUCAGCAUCCGCCAAACACUGCAGCAUCUUCCCCAGCGUUGAGAUCCAUGGAGUGGUGAGACACAUCCAGUGGACGCCCAGGGAGAUGGAGGUGUACAUCAGGCACUUGGAGAAGGUGUUAAGGCGCUAUGUCCAGAGGCUGCAGUGGCUGCUGUCCGGUCCAGUCCUCUGCAGUAGGACCUGGUAUAGACAGUCCAUGGACAGGGGCGUCAUGAUGACUGCUGCUUCAGGGAGCCGCCGACUGUUUGGCACCGUUUUGGAGAGCAAAGUAUGCAUAUUGCUGGACACGUCAGGGUCCAUGGGCCCCUACCUGCAGCAGGUGAAGACAGAGCUGGUUUUGCUGAUUUGGGAACAGCUGCGGAAGUGCUGUGACAGUUUUAACCUGCUCAGCUUUGCAGAGAGCCUUCAGUCAUGGCAGGACACGCUGGUGGAGACCACAGAUGCAGCGUGUCAUGAGGCUAUGCAAUGGGUGACCCACCUGCAAGCUCAGGGCAGCACCUCCAUCUUGCAAGCAUUGCUGAAAGCUUUCAGUUUCCAUGAUCUGGAAGGAUUGUACCUCCUGACCGACGGAAAGCCAGACACAAGCUGCAGCCUUGUCCUAAAUGAAGUCCAAAAACUCAGGGAGAAAAGAGAUGUGAAAGUGCACACCAUUUCCUUGAACUGCUCAGACAGAGCGGCGGUUGAGUUCCUGAGAAAGCUGGCUUCCUUCACCGGCGGACGCUAUCACUGCCCUGUGGGUGAGGACACACUCUCCAAAAUUCACAGCCUGCUGACCAAAGGCUUCAUCAAUGAAAAGGAUCCCACAUUGCCACCAUUUGAAGGAGAUGAUUUAAGGAUCCUGGCCCAGGAGAUCACCAAGGCCAGAAGCUUCCUCUGGCAGGCCCAAUCCUUCAGAUCCCAACUCCAGAAGAAAAAUGAUGCAGAACCAAAGGUCACUCUUUCCUAGAGAAGUGUUCUCAGAAAAGUCAUCCUGCAAAGGACCACUCACUGAGCAAAUCUCAGCCCCGAGGGCAGGAUGGGAUGAAAUGCUGUGACCUGCAGGAAACAUGAUUCCUGGUACCAGGACUCUCUGGAAGCUGAGGAAGGAAAGACUUUGUCUUUUGUGUGAGGGGCCAUUCCCGGGUCUUAAUCUAACUCUCCAGCCCUGUCCCGCAGCGCACUCUACUCUCCAGCCACUAGAUUGUCCCUCUCUGGGAAGCCCUAAACCAACCCCCUGCCUAAAUGGUGGUGCUUCUUGCAAACCAACCCCCUGCCUGAACGGUGCUUCUUGCCCCCUCUGCCUGGAGACUCCUGCUCAUCCAUCAAGGCACAGCUCAAAUGACAUCAGCUCCCUGGGACCUAUCUAGAGCGAGGGGCCUCCAGUCUUUCUCUUGCAGCAUCCUGACCACGCAGACCUCUCGCACUCAGCACUCUAUGUCACGCCACCUUGCUCGCUGAUCUAACUCUUCUCCUUGAUGGUGAGCUCCUUCGGGAUGAGACUGGUGUCCCAGGAUCUGCAGGUCCCCAGAAGCUGCCACAUAGGAGACACAUGGUGAACAGUGAGCAGGCGGCUGAGCUGUGAGAGCCUAGCUCUGGAAAGCAGCUGAUGGGGUGGUCUCCACCCUGGUUCAUAAGAGGCUAAUGCAGAGUCACAGUCAGCCCAUCCUGGGGGAAGAAGAAACAAGUGAGCCUCAGCACCACCCUCCAUCCCUGCCCAACCAAACUGAAGUGAAGGCUGCUCAUCUGGGUUCAUUUUCUAAAAUUAAAAACAAUUAAUUUUAUUCUACUAAUAGGAUCAACAUGACUUUAACUGUUUGAAGUGAUCAUUGGCGUGUGUGUGUGUGCAUAAAUUUUUAGUGACAUAAAACUUUAUUAAAAGACUCAUACCAUAAUAAAGAAUUUCAAUAAGAAAAA